CCUUUCCGCUCCCAGGGGCGUUGGGAACGGUUGUAGGACGUGGCUCUUUAUUCGUGAGUUUUCCAUUUACCUCCGCUGAACCUAGAGCUUCAGACGCCCUAUGGCGUCCGCCUCGACCCAACCGGCGGCCUUGAGCGCUGAGCAAGCAAAGGCCUCAAUCCACUAAUUCCUUGCGCUCUCCGCUGGGCCCGCUGUCUGUUCUCCGACGCCUACCCGGGACGCCUCCCUGGGAUGCUUCUGGCGCGCAGUGGUCCUCGCGGAGGUGAUCCAGGCGUUCUCCGCCCCGGAGAAUGCAGUGCGCAUGGACGAGGCUCGGGAUAACGCCUGCAACGACAUGGGUAAGAUGCUGCAAUUCGUGCUGCCCGUGGCCACGCAGAUCCAGCAGGAGGUUAUCAAAGCCUAUGGCUUCAGCUGCGACGGGGAAGGUGUCCUUAAGUUUGCUCGCUUGGUCAAGUCCUACGAAGCCCAGGAUCCUGAGAUCGCCAGCCUGUCAGGCAAGCUGAAGGCGCUGUUUCUGCCGCCCAUGACCCUGCCACCCCAUGGGCCUGCUGCUGGUGGCAGCGUGGCCGCCUCCUGAGAGUUGGCCCUCCCUUGUGCCACUGCCAGGGGAGGAAAGGCCUUGAUGUUCCAGACAAUAAUAAAUGCGCCUGUGACUUA